UGGAGCUCAGAGAGGUUAAGCAACUUGCCCGAGGUCACACAGCUGGUAAGUGUGGAGCCAGAAUUUGAACCCAGAUCCACCUGACUCCAAACCGUGCUCUAAAUGCAUAUGCUGCCUUCCAAUGAAUGAAUGAAAGGUGAGAUUUUACUGGGCCAUGUAGGGGCUAGAGAAACAAGCCUGGUAGGCAGAGAGAGCGCAAAGAAGAAGGCUUUUUCUGAAUUAGGGAAAAGCUCUGAGAACUCACGCUCGUGGAACAGACACUUACUGAACAUCUACUACAGGCCAGACAGUCUGCUGAGAUUACCAAGAUGAGUGAGAACUGCCCCCAAGGAGCUCACUGACUAAGAGGCUGGGAGAGCUGGUCAAGUGACAGGCACAUCAAGUAACAAACAUGCUGGCAUAGGAGAGGUGCUAUGGAAACACAGGGGAUAGGCAGCCAGCUCGGGCUGUAGUAGUGGGAGUUUUCCUGGAGGGGGCGAGACAGUGGCCACUGUGAUUACAGAAGAGGACCAGGGUCUUCUACAGCUUUGAUCCCCUCUCCACGCCCAUCCAUGAGAUGUGUGGAUUUUCCCACGCCUUUCAGAAGAGGAUUGUUGCCUCUGGUUAUAAGACCCUUCUCAAGUGCCUCUCAGGUAAAUUCUGCCGCCGGGAGCUGAUUGGCAUCAUGGGCCCCUCAGGGGCUGGCAAGUCUACAUUCAUGAACAUCUUGGCAGGAUACAGGGAGUCUGGAAUGAAGGGGCAGAUCCUGGUUAAUGGAAGGCCACGGGAGCUGAGGACCUUCCGCAAGAUGUCCUGCUACAUCAUGCAAGAUGACAUGCUGCUGCCGCACCUCACGGUGUUGGAAGCCAUGAUGGUCUCUGCUAACCUGAAGCUGAGUGAGAAGCAGGAGGUGAAGAAGGAGCUGGUGACAGAGAUCCUGACGGCACUGGGCCUGAUGUCGUGCUCCCACACGAGGACAGCCCUGCUCUCUGGCGGGCAGAGGAAGCGUCUGGCCAUCGCCCUGGAGCUGGUCAACAACCCGCCUGUCAUGUUCUUUGAUGAGCCCACCAGUGGUCUGGAUAGCGCCUCUUGUUUCCAAGUGGUGUCCCUCAUGAAGUCCCUGGCACAGGGGGGCCGUACCAUCAUCUGCACCAUCCACCAGCCCAGUGCCAAGCUCUUUGAGAUGUUUGACAAGCUCUACAUCCUGAGCCAGGGUCAGUGCAUCUUCAAAGGCGUGGUCACCAACCUGAUCCCCUAUCUAAAGGGACUCGGCUUGCAUUGCCCCACCUACCACAACCCGGCUGACUUCAUCAUCGAGGUGGCCUCUGGCGAGUAUGGAGACCUGAACCCCAUGUUGUUCAGGGCUGUGCAGAAUGGGCUGUGCGCUAUGGCUGAGAAGAAGAGCAGCCCUGAGAAGAACGAGGUCCCUGCCCCAUGCCCUCCUUGUCCUCCGGAAGUGGAUCCCAUUGAAAGCCACACCUUUGCCACCAGCACCCUCACACAGUUCUGCAUCCUCUUCAAGAGGACCUUCCUGUCCAUCCUCAGGGACACGGUCCUGACCCACCUACGGUUCAUGUCCCACGUGGUUAUUGGCGUGCUCAUCGGCCUCCUCUACCUGCAUAUUGGCGACGAUGCCAGCAAGGUCUUCAACAACACCGGCUGCCUCUUCUUCUCCAUGCUGUUCCUCAUGUUCGCCGCCCUCAUGCCAACUGUGCUCACCUUCCCCUUAGAGAUGGCGGUCUUCAUGAGGGAGCACCUCAACUACUGGUACAGCCUCAAAGCGUAUUACCUGGCCAAGACCAUGGCUGACGUGCCCUUUCAGGUGGUGUGUCCGGUGGUCUACUGCAGCAUUGUGUACUGGAUGACGGGCCAGCCCGCUGAGACCAGCCGCUUCCUGCUCUUCUCAGCCCUGGCCACCGCCACCGCCUUGGUGGCCCAAUCUUUGGGGCUGCUGAUCGGAGCUGCUUCCAACUCCCUACAGGUGGCCACUUUUGUGGGCCCAGUUACCGCCAUCCCUGUCCUCUUGUUCUCCGGCUUCUUUGUCAGCUUCAAGACCAUCCCCACUUACCUGCAAUGGAGCUCCUAUCUCUCCUAUGUCAGGUAUGGCUUUGAGGGUGUGAUCCUGACGAUCUAUGGCAUGGAGCGAGGAGACCUGACAUGUUUAGAGGAACGCUGCCCGUUCCGGGAGCCACAGAGCAUCCUCCGAGCGCUGGAUGUGGAGGAUGCCAAGCUCUACAUGGACUUCCUGGUCUUGGGCAUCUUCUUCCUAGCCCUGCGGCUGCUGGCCUACCUUGUGCUGCGUUACCGGGUCAAGUCAGAGAGAUAGAGGCUUGCCCCAGCCUGUACCCCAGCCCCUGCAGCAGGAAGCCCCCAGUCCCAGCCCUUUGGGACUGUUUUAACCUUAUAGACUUGGGCACUGGUUCCUGGCGGGGCUAUCCUCUCCUCCCUUGGCUCCUCCACAGGCUGGCUGUCGGACUGCGCUCCCAGCCUGGGCUCUGGGAGUGGGGGCUCCAGCCCUCCCCACUAUGCCCAGGAGUCUUCCCAAGUUGAUGCGGUUUGUAGCUUCCUCCCUACUCUCUCCAACACCUGCAUGCAAAGACUACUGGGAGGCUGCUGCCUCCUUCCUGCCCAUGGCACCCUCCUCUGCUGUCUGCCUGGGAGCCCUAGGCUCUCUAGGGCCCCACUUACAACUGACCAAAGUGGCCCCCUCUGGGGGUCCCCACCACACAAGUGUUUGUAAACUGGGCUGCUAUAAGGUUGGAGUUCCAGGGCUGGGCCCUGGUGGAGUCCACUGGAAGUCCCAUUAUGGAUGUUGAAAUGGACAGGGAAGGACUCUGGAAGUCUCUUCCUCCUCCUCCUCUUCUCUCCACCCCUAGACCCUGGCUGACUUGGACAAUCUGCCAGGACAGAAGCUGGGUUUUCUGUCUAGGUCACCACUCCCAAUCCUGGGGAUUGGAGAGGCCUGGGGCUGUGGGAUGCCCCAUCCCCCUCCCCAUCACCUUUGGUGGGGGCAGGGCCUGGUGGCACCUGUGCAAUAAUGUCUGUGUUUCUCUCCCACCUGCCACUGGAACUGGAGAAUGCACUUUAUUCUGGGCGGGGGGUGAGUGGGGGAAGACCCAACCCUCCUUUCUCGCUGCCCCUAACGCAUGCACGGUCUCGUGAUGCUCCCUCCCUCUCCGGAGUGACAGGCACAUACAUGAGAACAGGCCAUCUCAGCCCUACACACUUGCCAUCCCCUACAGCACAGAGGAAGAGUGAUGGUGGCAUGCUGGUGGUGGCGGGUGCUGGUGGGAGGACAGUGCCAACCUCCUCCUGGGGAUCCCAUGUUGGAGACUCUAAGGAUAAGGCUGGUGCUGCCCAGGGUGUCUACAGGAACUGCAGGUGUCUACCCCCAAGUCUUCCCUCCUCCCAAGCCAGGGGUGGCACAGGGCACUAGAUCCCUGGAGUUCAGGAACCAACACAAGCACAACCACGGGCAUAAGUUGGCCUUGGCCACUGCCACCCACGGCCCUCCUUUUGUGCUCCAUGCUGGCAUCUUCACUCCCCUACCCCUUCCCCAGCCACUGCUGCUCAUUCAAACUUCUGUCCAUGUCCCUCCACUGUUCCUAUCAGCAGGUGGCCCCUGGGCAUCAGAACAGCCUGCCCUGGGCACCAGGUGGCAGACACACUCAGAGCAUGUCUGGCUUUCCUGGUGGGUCCAGGCUCAUUCUGCUUCUGAUUUCCCCUCCCCCAGGGCUCAUUUUCCCCCUUUUUCCUGUACACAUCCCUGUCUACCUCCUCUCACCCUGCCACAGAUUCUUCCUAUCACACAGGGAUGCCAGUUGUAUUUGUGGGAUUUCACCCAUUAUUAAUAAAACCUAUAUUUAUACAGUAUGCAAUGUGUAAA